GCACUCUGCCGGCAACGCCGAGGCGCUUCUGCAUCUGUGGGCCGAGCAUUCUUCAGGUCAUCUGAACCUUCUGAGAAAACAUGGUCAACGUCUUGAAAGGAGUGCUUAUAGAAUGUGAUCCUGCCAUGAAGCAGUUUCUGCUGUACUUGGAUGAGUCCAAUGCCCUGGGGAAGAAGUUCAUCAUUCAAGACAUUGAUGACACUCACGUCUUUGUAAUAGCAGAAUUGGUUAAUGUCCUCCAGGAGCGAGUGGGUGAAUUAAUGGACCAAAAUGCUUUUUCCCUUACCCAGAAAUGAAAAUACUCAAUAUGGACCAUUUAGGAAUUAUAAGCAGCAACUGUGAAAGACUUGCCACUCAAUAUCUUAGGUGACUGAUUAGACAUAGAGGGUUGUUUUAGGAGCAUGCCACGGGAAAGACUGAGGGAUCAUGAUCAUUUGUUCAGAAAAAAAGCCCCUGAACUGAUUUUGUUACCAUAGAAUUUAAAAAAAAAAAAAGCUUUAACAGUUGGCUGUAAUUUGGCUUUUAUUAUCCUUUAUUAAAAUACAAAUGUCAAUGCUUUUCCUGCCUUUUUAAUACCAUGUCAGUGUAACAUAGGUAUUUAUUUUGCUCAUCCCUGUGAUCUGUGCAUUUUUGCUGCGUGGAUGUGAUUGUUUGGUUUCAGUUAGAAACGUCAUAGAUUUGCUGUUUGAAUAUGCCAAGGUGGGGACUUAGACAUUAUGUACGUCUCACAAAUCCUACCUGCAUACCAGUCAGCUCUAUUGAGGAAGACAAUGUAAAACUAAUGUAAACUACAGUUUGCAUUUCCCUGAAAACAGAAUAUUGUUUUUAAGAGGGUUAGAAACAACCAGUGGGAAAGGCACAUGCUGCUUUGUUUAGUUUUUCCUUGUUCAAACUUUGUUGGUCACAUUUUCCCAUCUGUAUUCUUUUUUAUUAAGAAAACAGCUUAGGGAGGCUGAGGUGGGAGGAUUGCUUGAGCCCAGGAGUCCGAGGUUGCUACAAAAACACCAUUGCACUCUGGCCUGGACAACAGAGAGACCCUGCCUCAAAAAAAAAAAAAAAAAAAAAAAAAAUUCUACUUGUACCUUAUUCCCUAUGAGAAUACUUAUCAAACUUAUCUAAAAAAGAAAAAUAGGAACAGCCAUAUGCAAAGUCAGCCCAACAGGAAAGGACAUAUUAGAUUAAAAUACAUUGCGGCCUGGGCUUAGUGGCUCACACCUGUAAUCCCAGCACUUUGGGAGGCUGAGGCAGGCAGAUCGCUUGAGUCCAGGAGUCGAAACCCUGUCUCUACAAAAAAAAAAAUACAAAAAUCUGCCUGUUGUCCCAGCCACUGGGGAGGCUGAGGUAGGAGGUCAAGGCUGCAGUGAACCUUGAUCAUUGCUACUGCCACUCCAGCCUAGGUGACAGAGUGAGACCCUGUCUCCAAAAAAAAAAGUGUAUAUGUAUGUGUGUAUAUAUAGCAAGAGAGAGUUCUGUGAUCAAUUGAAGGCAAAAACAGUAACACUGAGAGGGGCUUUGCUUCCCUUCCUGAAGAUCAUGUCAUUGGGGUGGGUUCCUGUAAAGGGAAUUUUCCAAGAGAAAAGAGAAUUUUCAUGACCUGUAGACUCUUACAAAUCCAUUUUACCUGCUUCCUUAUGGUAUGUUUAUUCAAAGCACCUGUGUACCAUAUUUAUUCACUUACACAGCAUUACUGAAUCUGGAAAUUUUCAGUUAGGUAUAUUUUACAUAAUUCCCACCCAUAUAACUCAGUCCAUACAGUUCACAGUUUUCAUUCCCUCAUAGCAAUGCAAAAAAUUUUGAUGAGUUACUACUACUAAAACUAGUUAAGUAAAAGAUGAUUCUUAAGAAUUUCCAGGCUGGGCACGGUGGCUCACGCCUGUAAUCCCAGCACUUUGGGAGGCUGAGGCAGGCAGCUCACGAGGUCAGGAGAUCGAGACCAUCCUGCUCGGUGAAACCCCAUCUCUAUUAAAAAUACAAAAAAUUAGCCGGGCCUGGUGGCGGGUGCCUGUAGUCCCAUCUACUCAGGAGGCUGAGGCAGGAGAAUGGCGUGAACCCGGGAGGCGGAGCUUGCAGUAAGCUGAGAUUGUGCCACUGCACUCCAGCCUGGGCGACAGAGGGAGACUCCAUCUCAAAAAAAAAAAAAAAAAAAAAUGAAUUUCCAGCUAUACCAAAAUGUUACUAAUGUAUCUUAUAUUUCAGGCAUGUCUAAAUCAACUUUUAGUAUGCCUCAGGCAUUUGUCACCAACCUUUUAUAUUAACAUGAAACUUAGAAAAUUUUUGAUAGAAUCCCAGAGUUCAAAAGGUAUUAGGAUUUUUGCCACUGAAGUAAAAAAGAGAAAAAAAGAUAUUUAUGAGAAAACUAUUGAACAGUGACUGUGUUGUACCCGAGCAAGUUAGAGGAACGCCACACUUUGAGACGAAUUUAAAAGUCCUUUAUUUAGCUGGCAGCCAAGAGGUGGCUCACACUUGGAAUUCUCUCAGCUCCGAGGAAGGGGCUUGAUUUUCCUUUAUACUUUGGUUUAGGAAGGGGACGGGAGCUCAGUUGCAACAAUUCUACAGAAGUAAAAACAUGCAAAAAAUUAAAAAGACAAAUGGUUACAGAGAAACAAACAGUUCCAGGUGCAGGGGCUCUAAAUCUAUCAUAAGAUGUCAGGUGUGGGGGCUCUGCCAGACACAAACUCAAGGCUUUAUGGUGUAUCUCUUGAGCGAAAUCCUGGGAACUUCGUACAUUGCUUGCUUCAGUACCUUAUGAGUUAAUUGGACUCUUUGAUAUGUUGAGAGUCAGCUUACACAAGUUAACUCCUUGAGGAAAGGGGGUGGGUAAGGAGUCCUUGAUGUCCUGUAAAUGAAGGAACCAAAUGGAGUUCCUCCGGCUUUCUCAGCUAAGGGAGAGCUUAUUCACAUGGAAACAAGGCUAGGUGAUUAAGGGAGAAAGGGACAGUCUGAAAACAAGGUUAGUAAAAACAAGGUUAGGUAUUAGAACUGCAAAGAGUAUUAAGUGAAAUAAGUGAAGGAAAAUAUGAGCUCUUAUUUUUAAAAAGUUGUGUUGGGGCAAAUGUUAAAUAUCUUUCUUUCUCUGGACAUUAUUAAGAAAGAUAGAGUGAUGUGAAUGAUAGGAAGCCCACCUGUAACCACUUAGCUGACAUGUCCAACUAUGGGUGAACAGGAAAUAAGCGACAUUCACCUAGGCUGUUUAUUGGAAUCUGACUAGCAUUAUUUGAUUUGGCAUACUUUACAUGUCCAGAACAAGGCUGUUGGUGCUUGGCACCAAGAAAUUUAUGACUUUUUUUUUUUUUUUAAAUAAAGUCCUAAAGGUAGCAUUAAAAUGACUUAACUGGAGGCAGGAGGAUCACUGAAGCCCAGGAGUUUGAAGCUGCAGUAAGCUAAGAAGGUGCCACUGCACUGCAGCCUGGAUGACAGAGUGAAACUUUGUCUCUUAAUAGAACUAUGGACUGAAGUUGUGAUAUUGAGUGUUAUAUUUCUCAAUAAAGGUUUUUUCUUUUAAUACUGUAUUAGGUCAAAUUCAAGGUCUUAAUUCCUUGAAUUCCAAUUUCCUUGUGAAAUUUCAUGUGAUUAAUUUAAAAUUCCAGGGAUCCUAUCUAACAUCACAGUUGAUGGAUAUAACAAUGUAUUUUGAGAAAUCAGUUUUGGUGAACAGUAACAGCAUUACUGAUAAUAGGCAACAAACACUACUGCAUUUUAUUUCUGAUAGGCAUUAUAGGUGGUAAUCCAAAUGAUUAAUGAUUUUAUUGCUCUUUACAUUUUCUAGAACAGGUGAUUUGACAUAAUUGUACUUUUUUCUGAGAAGUUGGUAGUGUACUUACUACUCUAUUUUGCAGUUAUACAAUAAAUCUUACUUAGCUGACAACUAGGAGUAAAAGCUCUGACAAAAAGCCUCUGCUGUAACUAAAAUACUGAGAUCAUUCUAUCUUAACAAACUUAACAGAUGGGGAAGGGGUAUAUUUUAAAGAUGGAGAAAUGAUGCAGUUUGCAAAUAUAGUCAAUAAAUAUUCUCAAGUGUACGUAGCUCAAUUUCAUUUGCAGCAAAGAUAACACUGAAAUGUCUAUGGAUGAGAUUAUUGGAUAAACUUUUUUAAAAACACUGUUCUCAAGAUAGGCAAGUGAUUAAGAGCACUGACUGGGCCGGGCGCGGUGGCUCACGUCUAUAAUCCUAGCACUUUGGGAGGCCGAGGCGGGCAAAUCACAAGGUCAGGAGAUCAAAACAAUCCUGGCUAACAAGGUGAAACCCCGUCUCUACUAAAAAUACAAAAAAAUUAGCUGGGCAUGGUGGUGGACGCCUGUAGUCCCAGCUACUCGGGAGGCUGAGGCAGGAGAAUGGUGUAAUCCCGGGAGGUGGAGGUUGCAGUGAGCCGAGAUCGUGCCACUGCACUCCAGCCGGGGUGACAGAGCGAGACUCCCACCCAUCUCAAAAAAAAUAAAAAUGAAAAGCACUGAUUGAAUCUAGAUUCCUUGAGUCCAAGUGUCAGAUCUCUGCUUACUAGCUCUGGGAUCUCAGAUGUUUCGUUGAUUGGAUUUCUUUGUGCUCAUUUGUGUAAACAGGAAUGCCCGUCUUUAAAGACUAUUAAAAUGAAUGUGAGUUAACACACAAGAGGUCUUCAAAAAGUUGAUGGAAAAUGCAUAUUAUGAAAAAAAUUAUGCAUAGAUUUCAAAAAUCUUUGCAGCAAAAUAAACUCAUCAUUAUAACAUGUCUGAACAGGAUCUAGUUUGAGGCACUAAGAAGGAUAUCAGUUUAAAUAGAGCCCCUGUCAGAACAAUAUGAAUUCUGCUAAAACUGAAGCAAGAACAAACAUCAAAUUUAUGGCAAAGCUUAGGUGGAAGAAUGGUGCAAUCAUUGAUGCUUUGCAAAAAGUUUAUGGGAACAACGCCCCAAGGAAAUCAGUUUACAAAUGGAUAAUUCAUUUUAAGAAAGGACAAGACAAUGUUGAAGAUGAAACCUACAGCAGCAGACCAUGCCACUUCGUGAGGAAAAAAUUAUCUCAUUCAUGCCCUACUUGAAGAGGACCAAUGAUUAACAGCAGAAACGAUAGCCAACACAAUAUGCUCCUCAGUUGGUUCAGCUUUUAUAAAUCUGACUGAAAAAUUAAAGUUGAGCACACUUUCCACUCAAUGGAUACCAAAACCAUCCAGCCCAGGUCAGCUGCAGACAAAAGCAGAGCUUUCGAUGGAAAUGUCAAACAAGUGAGAUCAAGAUCCUGAAGCAUUUCUUCAAAGAAUUGUAGCAAAAACAGACUUUUAAAACCUUGAAUUCAGAGACAGGUAUAAAGACUGCUUGGUGAUUUUGAAAGGACUGAGAUCAUUUUGGGAGAGAUCAUCUUCAGAAAAUGACCAGAUACAACAAGAAUUUAACAUGGCAGCCAAACCAACCCACUAACACACAUUUAAAUAAGAUACCCAAAUGCAGAAAGAAAAGCACAGUCGUCAUGCAAAAUAGUCACUACUCAUUCAAAAACUCUAUAGUUGUCUGAGUCGUUAUGCUCAAAAUAUCCAAUAAUAUUUCUUUUGCUGAGCUGUAAAAUAAUUAUUUUGCAAACAUAAAAGAAAAAAAAAAGAAUUGUAACAGAAACAUGGCUUUACCAGUAUGACCCUCAAGACAAAAUACAAAACAAUGGCUACCAAGAGGUGGAAGUGGCCCAGUCACAGCAAGAGCAGAUUGAUCAAGAGCAAAGGUCAUGGUAACAGUUUUUUGGAUCCUCAAGUCAUUUUGCUUGUUGACUUUUUGGAGGGCCAAAUAAAGAUAUCAUCUGCUUAUUAUGAGAGUGUUUCGAGAGAAAUCCAAAGCUUAGCAGAGAAACGCCUGGGAAAGCUUCACCAGAGGGUCUUCCACCGUGACAGUUCCCCUGCGCAUUCCUCUCAUAAAGCAAGGGCAGUUUAGCUAGAAUUUCUAUCAAAAAUCAUUAGGUAUCCAUCUCCCAGUCCUGAUUUGGCUCCUUCUGACUUCUUUUUGUUUCCCAAUCUUAAAAAAAUCCCUGAAGGGCACCUGUUUUUCUUCAGCUAAUAAAAAAGACAUGGUUAAUUUCCCAGGACCCUCAGUUCUUUAGGGAUAGACUGAAUGGCUGGUAUCAUUGCUUGAACUUAAUGGAGCUUAUGUUGAGAAAUAAAAGAAAUUAUAUUUUAUUUUUAUCUUUUAAUUCUAUUUUUCCAUGAACUUUUUGAAGUCCCCUCAGAUAUAAAGCAGAACGUUAUGAAACUGAGUUACCUUGAAUCUAGAAGAGUACAAUGAUAAAGGGGAAGAUAGAAACACACACAUAUGCGUUGUUUUCCCCACUUUCACAAUGCCGUGCAGAAACUAACAGAUGAAGGAGGAGAAUCCCUAAAAACAGAGCAUUGGGUAGCUAGUCCACCAGCGGUCUGAUGCUUUCAUUGAUCUCAAAACUGUCUCUGAGUAACUCUACCAGGAAAGUUGUCUGGAGGGUUAACAUUUCUGAAACCAUUUUUAUCUUUGCCUUCAUUCUUGAAUGAUAAUUAGUCUCGAAUGUUUGGAUCACAAUCCAUUGAAAGACUAGGCUAUUUUUUCACUGUCCUCAGACAUUUACUGAGUCCAGUUUGGACUUUAUUUUAUUUUAUUUUUUUUGAAACAAGAUCUCGCUCUGUUGCUCAGGCUGAAGUGCAAUAGCGCAAACUCGGCUCACUGCAACCUCCCAGGUUCAAGCAAUUCUCGUGCCUCAGCCAUCCCUAUAGGCAUGCGCCACCACACUUUGCUAAUCUUGUAUUUUUGGUAGAGACGGGGUUUGCACCAUGUUGGCCAGGCUGGUCUCGAACUCCCAACCUCAAGUAAUCUGGCCUCCCAAAGUGGUGGGAUUACAGGCGUGAGCCAGCGCGCCCGGCCUGGACUUAACUUCUGAAGAACUCUUUCUGUUUAGAUUGCAGGAGCGUUCUCUCGGCUCAUCUCUUGUUUUCUCACCCAGCUGUUCUUCUUCUAGUUGGCCAUCAUUCUUCAUCCCUCCCUCCCUUUCCUGCAGUUAAUUAUUUCUUUGAAAUUUUAAAACUUCUUAAUGUUGCCUGGAAUACAUGAGUCUUCCUGAUCUCUUCAAACGGGGUUUGUUUUGUUUUGCUUUGGGGAGAAUUCUUUUGACGUUUUUGAAUAAGCUGUUAACAACUUUAAUACCUGUCUUGUUUGUUUUCUUCAGAAAUUUGUUAAUUCUCCAUGAUUAGCACCUUUAUGUGGUUAUCUCAUUAUUUUCAUUCCUUUUUAAUUCUCUGUUUUAGGAAUGCUUGUCAAAUUCGUCACUAAAAUUGAUUUACUUUCUUGAAAACCUGUUUCUGCUGCUCCCAACAUGAUUUAAUCUUGGCUACUGAGCUUUUGGUUACGUUGCACUCCCUUUAAAAUUACUCCGUUUAAGUACAGUGUUCACUCUUUGGGUAAUGUGUACAAUAGAAGCCCAAUCCCCACCUAUACCCAAUAUAUCCAUGGGACAAGCAUGUACAUGCACCCCCUGAGUCUAAAAUAAAAAUUUUAAAAAAACUA